AGGGGAAGUCCCGGCGCCCGGCGAAACCACCCUCCCGUGCAGCCGAGCCCAGCCGCUCUCCGGCCGCCGUCCCCGGCGGCCCCAUGCCCCGAUGCCCCGCGGGGGCCAUGGACGAGGGGCCCGUGGACCUGCGCACCCGGCCCAAGGCCGCCGGACUCCCGGGCGCCGCGCUGCCGCUCCGCAAGCGCCCGCUGCGCGCGCCCUCCCCGGAGCCCGCCGCUCCCCGCGGCGCUGCGGGCCUUGUCGUCCCCCUGGACCCUCUGCGCGGCGGCUGCGACCUGCCGGCGGUCCCCGGGCCCCCCCACGGCCUGGCCCGGCCGGAGGCGCUUUACUACCCCGGAGCCUUACUGCCUUUGUACCCCACUCGGGCCAUGGGCUCCCCGUUUCCUCUGGUGAACCUGCCUACACCCCUAUACCCCAUGAUGUGCCCCAUGGAACACCCCCUUUCUGCUGACAUCGCCAUGGCCACCCGUGCAGAUGAGGACGGAGACACGCCUCUCCAUAUUGCUGUGGUGCAGGGUAACCUGCCAGCUGUGCACCGGCUGGUCAACCUCUUCCAGCAGGGGGGCCGGGAGCUCGACAUCUACAACAACCUACGGCAGACACCGCUCCACCUGGCUGUGAUCACCACAUUACCGUCUGUGGUCCGGCUCCUGGUGACAGCUGGUGCCAGCCCCAUGGCGCUGGACCGCCAUGGCCAGACGGCCGCUCACCUGGCGUGCGAGCACCGCAGCCCGACCUGCCUGCGAGCCCUGCUGGACAGCGCAGCUCCGGGCACGUUGGACCUGGAGGCCCGCAAUUAUGACGGGCUCACCGCCCUGCACGUGGCAGUGAACACCGAGUGCCAAGAAACCGUGCAGCUCUUGCUAGAGCGCGGUGCCGACAUCGACGCAGUGGACAUUAAGAGCGGCCGCUCCCCGCUCAUCCACGCCGUGGAAAACAACAGCCUUAGCAUGGUGCAGCUGCUGCUGCAGCACGGCGCCAACGUGAACGCGCAAAUGUACUCCGGCAGCUCCGCCCUGCACUCAGCGUCCGGCCGCGGGCUCCUCCCGCUGGUGCGCACGCUGGUCCGCAGCGGCGCUGACAGCAGCCUCAAGAACUGCCACAACGACACGCCGCUCAUGGUGGCGCGCAGCCGCAGGGUGAGCCGGGGCAGCUGUGGACAUGCCCCUUGCACACGUGUGUCCGCGGGCUGGUUGCAGGUCAUCGACAUCCUGAGGGGGAAGGCCACCCGGCCUGCUUCCACCUCCCAGCCAGACCCCUCCCCUGACCGGAGCGCCAACACCUCCCCCGAGAGCAGCAGCCGCCUCAGCUCCAAUGGUCUUCUCUCCGCAUCACCAUCCUCCUCACCCUCCCAGUCUCCCCCCAGGGACCCCCCUGGAUUCCCCAUGGCUCCUCCCAAUUUCUUCCUUCCUUCCCCAUCUCCACCCGCCUUCCUGCCCUUUGCUGGGGUCCUCCGAGGCCCUGGCCGGCCGGUGCCCCCCUCCCCAGCUCCAGGAGGCAGCUGAGGGGGAUGGGGGGGCAGAUCUUGGACUCAUGAGGAGGGGCCCCCCUGCCCUGUGGGGUCAACCCUUCUGGAAACUGUGAAGAUCUCACUCUGCCCCCCCCCCCCAUCUUCGGGACCAGGAUUUGCACAGAAGCACAUGCACCUACCCAUACACCCCCUCUUCUGAGCACAGAUGUUCCCCCAUCUCGCUCCCUCCCAGGACUCUGACCCCAGCAUUCUCAGGCACCAGUCCCUGUCCGGAAUGCCACCCACAUCUUCCAUUUCCAUGUCCCCUCCCAGAGCUGGUGGACCCAGGGAACAGCCACUCCCCUCCACUCUCUACCAGAUAACUGAGGAGGGGAGAGGUGGGCCGUAACGGGCACGGAUCACGAUGUAAAUUAUUAAGCAUUUUGGUUGGAUUUCUUUUGUAAUAAACUAUUUUUGUACCAUA